GUCAGGGCCAGGGAUGUAGUAGGACUAGGGGCAGAGCCGGCACUAGGGCUGAGCCAGGGCAGAGCAGGAGAGAUUACUUUAGGCUAUUACUAAAAUUUUUAUUUUAGAUUUUUAAGAUAACUAUAGUAGUAGUAAUGUCUAUACUAUGUUGUUUGUAAUAGUAAUAAUACUUGCAGUAAUCACUAAAUUUUAACUAAUACUAUCUUUGCUUCCAGUAGUGUUCUAUGAGUAUAAUUUUAUCAACAUGUAAAUAUGUGAGGCAUUGAUUCUCAUAAUAAUUCUAUAUGCUAGGUACUUAAAGCAUCCCCAUUUUCCAAAUGUAGGAAACAGGCAAAAAGAAGGUAAAUACUUGGCCAGAUUACUCCUGUAAUCCCAGCACUUUGGGAGGCCAAGGCAGGCAGAUGGCUUGAGCUCAGGAGUUUGGAACCAGCCUGGGCAACAUUGUGAAACCCCAUCUCUACUAAAAAUGCACAAAAAGAACUAAUUUAAGUUUCUUGUAGGAUUCUGGUUAUAAAACACUGGUCAAACACACAGGGCAUGGAUAGGGCAGGGCCAGGGACAAGGUCAGGCCAGGAAGGGGCCAGGGCCAAGGCAGGGCCAGAGCUGGACUUGGAGGUGUCCUGGUCUGAUUUGCCCUGCCCCAACGUUGGCCCAGCCCUGCUCUGGCACGUCCUGUCAUGCCCUGUCCCUGGCCUGAGCAUUGGCCCUGGCCCUGUCCUGCUUCUGGCCCUGCCCCGGAGUUGACCAGGCACUGCCAUGGCCCAGUCCUGCAUUGCCCUGCCCUCCUCUGCCCUGGUGCUACCAUGGCCCUGCUUGGGCCCUAGCUCUGCCUCGACUCUGGACCUGCCCUGACUCUGCUCAGCCCUGGAUCUACCCUGACUCUGCCUUGGUGUUGCCCUCCCAUCUCUAUGGCCUGGCUCUGGCCAUGCCUUGCACAGACCAUGCUCUGCCCUGCGUGCCCCAGCCUGGGCCCAGCCCUCAUCCUACCAUAUUCCUGACCCCAGCCAUACCCUUGUUCUCGCCAUGACCCUGCCGUGGCCCUCUCCUGGCCCUUCCUUGAUCCUGCCCUGCCCUUCCAUGCCCUGGCCUUGCCCUCACCCUGCAUUGGCCCUGCACUGGUCCUGCCCUGCCCUGGCACUGCCUUGGCCCCGGCCCUGCCUUCUUCCUGGCCUUGCCUUUGCCCUGCCCUGGCCUGACCCCAGGCCUACUGAGUCCAUGAGAUGGCCCUGGACCUGCCUUGCCAUCCUCUGUCCUGGCCCUAUAUUGUCCCCACCAUGCUCUGGUCCAGCGCUUGCCCUAGCCCUGUUGCUAGUCCUGCCACUGCUAUGGCCCUGCUCUGUUUUUGGCCGUGCCCUGUGCUACCCUAGCCCUGCCCUGCCUUGGCCUUGGCCCUACCAUGGCCUUCUCUUACCCUGGCCUGGCCCUACCCUGGCCUUUUCUACCCUGGCCUUGCCCUUCCCUGGUCUUGCCCUGCCCUGGCCUUGGCUUUGCCUUAUCCUGGUCCUGGUUCUGCCCUGACCCUGGCCUUGCUCUGGAUCCUCUCUGGUUCUGCUUUCUCCCUGGCCCUGCCCUUGCUCUGGCCCUGUCCCUGGACCAGCCUUGACCCUGACCCUGACAAUCCCCAGGUCUGACACUGGCCAUGCUUGGCCCUGGCCCCUCCUUUUGGCCCUGC